GCAGGCGCGCCGAGAUGGCCGCGCUCCUGGCCGCCUAGAGCCGGAGCGGCCCGCGGAGCUGCGGAGGCAGCCAUGGUCGGGGCGCUGUGCGGCUGCUGGUUCCGCCUGGGCGGGGCCCGCCCGCUCAUCCCGUUGGGCCCGACUGUGGUACAGACCUCCAUGAGCCGGUCCCAGGUAGCCCUGCUGGGCCUGAGUCUGCUGCUCAUGCUCCUACUGUAUGUGGGGCUGCCAGGCCCCCCUGAGCAGACUUCCUGCCUCUGGGGAGACCCCAAUGUCACAGUCCUGGCUGGUCUCACCCCUGGCAACUCGCCCAUCUUUUACCGCGAGGUGCUCCCACUCAACCAGGCACACAGGGUGGAGGUGGUGCUGCUUCAUGGAAAGGCCUUUAACUCUCACACGUGGGAGCAGCUGGGCACACUGCAGCUACUGUCACAGAGGGGCUACCGGGCCGUGGCCCUUGACCUUCCAGGUUUUGGGAACUCGGCACCUUCAAAGGAGGCAAGCACAGAGGCAGGGCGGGCAGCGCUGCUGGAGCGGGCGCUGCGGGACCUGGAGGUACAGAAUGCCGUGUUGGUGAGCCCCUCGCUGAGUGGCCACUAUGCCCUGCCCUUCCUGAUGCGAGGCCACCACCAGCUACAUGGAUUUGUGCCCAUCGCACCCACCUCCACCCAGAACUACACCCAGGAGCAAUUCUGGGCUGUGAAGACUCCAACCCUUAUCCUGUAUGGAGAGCUGGACCACAUCCUGGCUCGAGAGUCACUGCGGCAGCUCCGCCACCUGCCCAACCACUCUGUGGUGAAGCUACGCAAUGCAGGCCAUGCCUGUUACCUCCACAAGCCGCAAGACUUCCACCUUGUCCUGCUUGCCUUCCUUGACCAUCUACCUUGAACUAACCCACUCCCAGCUCCCAGCCUGGCAUGAGCUUGGACAGUCUGGACCGCCACCCUCCCUGAACCAGGGAGACAGCCUCUGGGAUUGGAGGCCAGAGGCCAGGGUCAGACCCAGCCAGGACUCCUCAUUUCAUCUCACAGACACAAUAAAAAAGCAUAUUUGUCCUGCCUGGGAA